ACCUGGGGACCCUGGAGCCAGUGGAGCCCCUGCAGCCGGACCUGUGGAGGGGGUGUCAGCUUCCGGGAGCGCCCCUGCUACUCCCAGAGGGGUUGUUCCUGAGAACCCUAUGUGAGGAGGAAUGAGAGACCAGGAAUGAUCCUAAGAGCCUUAUACUGAUGUCCUGCUUAGAUCGCAGGAUGGCUGUGCCAAGCGGGUGGGUAUUAUAUCUCAUGCACCUCGGGUCUUCUCUGGGAAUCUGCCUAAGAUGCAGUGGAGUGGUCCCGCCUUAAAUCCAAACUAUAGGGUGGGUAGGGCUCUGAGUCCCGCUUCUCUGGAGUACCAACAUGGGUCGCUCACUCCCACCUGGGGGAUUUACGGGGUGGGGUCGGGGGACACCCUCUCACCUUGCUGCUCCCACUGGAGAGUCCCGCAGAAGUUGGGGCCUGCAGAGAGCCCCAGAACGGGGGCAGGGACGUUGGGUCUCGGUCAGGUCUUCCCGGUGCUCUGGUCCCGCAGGAGAGAUGGAGGCUCCAGCUGCGUGGGCCCCGCCCGGAGCCACCGCUCUUGUCGCACGGAGAGCUGCCCCGACGGCGCCCGGGACUUCCGGGCCGAGCAGUGCGCGGAGUUCGACGGAGCGGAGUUCCAGGGGCGGCGGUAUCGGUGGCUGCCCUACUACAGCGCCCCAAACAAGUGUGAACUGAACUGCAUUCCCAAGGGGGAGAACUUCUACUACAAGCACAGGGAGGCUGUGGUUGAUGGGACGCCCUGCGAGCCUGGCAAGAGGGAUGUCUGUGUGGAUGGCAGCUGCCGGGUUGUCGGCUGUGAUCACGAGCUGGACUCGUCCAAGCAGGAGGACAAGUGUCUGCGGUGUGGGGGUGACGGCACGACCUGCUACCCCGUCGCAGGCACCUUUGACGCUAAUGACCUCAGCCGAGGCUACAACCAGAUCCUCAUAGUUCCCAUGGGUGCCACCAGCAUCCUCAUCGACGAGGCUGCUGCCAGCAGGAACUUCCUGGCUGUGAAGAAUGUUCGUGGGGAAUACUACCUCAAUGGGCACUGGACCAUCGAGGCGGCCCGGGCCCUGCCAGCAGCCAGCACCAUCCUGCAUUACGAGCGGGGUGCUGAGGGGGACCUGGCCCCUGAGCGACUCCAUGCCCGGGGCCCCACCUCGGAGCCCCUGGUCAUCGAGCUCAUCAGCCAGGAGCCCAACCCCGGUGUGCACUAUGAGUACCACCUGCCCCUGCGCCGCCCCAGCCCCGGCUUCAGCUGGAGCCACGGCUCAUGGAGUGACUGCAGCGCGGAGUGUGGCGGAGGUCACCAGUCCCGCCUGGUGUUCUGCACCAUCGACCAUGAGGCCUACCCCGACCACAUGUGCCAGCGCCAGCCACGGCCAGCUGACCGGCGUUCCUGCAAUCUUCACCCUUGCCCGGAGACCAAGCGCUGGAAGGCAGGGCCAUGGGCACCCUGCUCAGCCUCCUGUGGAGGAGGCUCCCAGUCCCGCUCCGUGUACUGCAUCUCGUCUGACGGGGCCGGCAUCCAGGAGGCCGUGGAGGAGGCUGAGUGUGCCGGGCUGCCUGGGAAGCCCCCUGCCAUUCAGGCCUGUAACCUGCAGCGCUGUGCAGCCUGGAGCCCGGAGCCCUGGGGAGAGUGUUCUGUCAGUUGUGGCGUUGGCGUCCGGAAGCGGAGCGUUACUUGCCGGGGUGAAAGGGGUUCUUUGCUCCAUACCGCAGCGUGCUCCUUGGAAGACCGGCCACCUCUGACUGAGCCCUGUGUGCAUGAGGACUGCCCCCUCCUCAGUGACCAGGCCUGGCAUGUUGGCACCUGGGGUCUAUGCUCCAAGAGCUGCAGCUCGGGCACUCGGAGGCGACAGGUCAUCUGUGCCAUUGGGCCGCCCAGCCACUGCGGGAGCCUGCAGCACUCCAAGCCUGUGGAUGUGGAGCCUUGUAACACGCAGCCCUGUCAUCUCCCCCAGGAGGUCCCCAGCAUGCAGGAUGUGCACACCCCUGCCAGCAACCCCUGGAUGCCGUUGGGCCCUCAGGAGUCCCCUGCCUCAGACUCCAGAGGCCAGUGGUGGGCAGCCCAGGAACACCCCUCAGCCAGGGGUGACCACAGGGGAGAACGAGGUGACCCCAGGGGCGACCAAGGCACCCACCUGUCAGCCCUGGGCCCCGCUCCCUCUCUGCAGCAGCCCCCAUACCAGCAACCCCUGCGGUCGGGCUCAGGGCCCCACGACUGCAGACACAGUCCUCACGGGUGCUGCCCCGAUGGCCACACGGCAUCUCUCGGGCCUCAGUGGCAAGGCUGCCCUGGGGCCCCCUGUCAGCAGAGCAGGUACGGGUGCUGCCCUGACAGGGUAUCUGUCGCUGAGGGGCCCCAUCACGCUGGCUGCACAAAGUCGUAUGGUGGUGACAGCACCGGGGGCAUGCCCAGGUCAAGGGCAGUGGCUUCUACAGUCCACAACACCCACCAGCCCCAGGCCCAGCAGAAUGAGCCCAGUGAGUGCCGGGGCUCCCAGUUUGGCUGUUGCUAUGACAACGUGGCCACUGCAGCCGGUCCUCUUGGGGAAGGCUGUGUGGGCCAGCCCAGCCAUGCCUACCCCGUGCGGUGCCUGCUGCCCAGUGCCCAUGGCUCUUGCGCAGACUGGGCUGCCCGCUGGUACUUCGUUGCCUCUGUGGGCCAAUGUAACCGCUUCUGGUAUGGCGGCUGCCAUGGCAAUGCCAAUAACUUUGCCUCGGAGCAAGAGUGCAUGAGCAGCUGCCAGGGAUCUCUCCAUGGGCCCCGUCGUCCCCAGCCUGGGGCUUCUGGAAGGAGCACCCACACGGAUGGUGGCGGCAGCAGUCCUGCAGGCGAGCAGGAACCCAGCCAGCACAGGACAGGGGCCGCGGUGCAGAGAAAGCCCUGGCCUUCUGGUGGUCUCUGGCGGCAAGACCAACAGCCUGGGCCAGGGGAGGCCCCCCACACCCAGGCCUUUGGAGAAUGGCCAUGGGGGCAGGAGCUUGGGUCCAGGGCCCCUGGACUGGGUGGAGAUGCCGGAUCACCAGCGCCACCCUUCCACAGCUCCUCCUACAGGAUUAGCUUGGCAGGUGUGGAGCCCUCGUUGGUGCAGGCAGCCCUGGGGCAGUUGGUGCGGCUCUCCUGCUCAGACGACACUGCCCCGGAAUCCCAGGCUGCCUGGCAGAAAGAUGGCCAGCCCAUCUCCUCUGACAGGCACAGGCUGCAGUUCGACGGAUCCCUGAUCAUCCACCCCCUGCAGGCAGAGGACGCGGGCACCUACAGCUGUGGCAGCACCCGGCCAGGCCGCGACUCCCAGAAGAUCCAACUUCGCAUCAUAGGGGGUGACAUGGCCGUGCUGUCUGAGGCUGAGCUGAGCCGCUUCCCUCAGCCCAGGGACCCAGCUCAGGACUUUGGCCAAGCGGGGGCUGCUGGGCCCCUGGGGGCCAUCCCCUCUUCACACCCACAGCCUGCAAACAGGCUGCGUUUGGACCAGAACCAGCCCCGGGUGGUGGAUGCCAGUCCAGGCCAGCGGAUCCGGAUGACCUGCCGUGCCGAAGGCUUCCCGCCCCCAGCCAUCGAGUGGCAGAGAGAUGGGCAGCCUGUCUCUUCUCCCAGACACCAGCUGCAGCCUGAUGGCUCCCUGGUCAUUAGCCGAGUGGCUGUAGAAGAUGGCGGCUUCUACACCUGUGUCGCUUUCAAUGGGCAGGACCGAGACCAGCGAUGGGUCCAGCUCAGAGUUCUGGGGGAGCUGACAAUCUCAGGACUGCCCCCUACUGUGACAGUGCCAGAGGGUGAUACGGCCAGGCUAUUGUGUGUGGUAGCAGGAGAAAGUGUGAACAUCAGGUGGUCCAGGAACGGGCUACCUGUGCAGGCUGAUGGCCACCGUGUCCACCAGUCCCCAGAUGGCACGCUGCUCAUUUACAACUUGCGGGCCAGGGAUGAGGGCUCCUACACGUGCAGUGCCUACCAGGGGAGCCAGGCAGUCAGCCGCAGCACCGAGGUGAAGGUGGUCUCACCAGCACCCACCGCCCAGCCCAGGGACCCUGGCAGGGACUGCGUCGACCAGCCAGAGCUGGCCAACUGUGAUUUGAUCCUGCAGGCCCAGCUUUGUGGCAAUGAGUAUUACUCCAGCUUCUGCUGUGCCAGCUGUUCACGUUUCCAGCCUCACGCUCAGCCCAUCUGGCAGUAGGGAUGAAGGCUAGUUCCAGCCCCAGUCCAAAAUAGUUCAUAGGGCUAGGGAGAAAGGAAGAUGGACUCUUGGCUUCCUCUCUCUGGCUGGCAAAGGGAGUUAUCUUCUGGAAUACAUUAGCUCUUUCAAAAACCCACCCAGUGUUUAGCCUCAACGGCAGCCAGUUACCAGCUUCUCUCUGUAGCCUUCAGCAGUGUUUGCAUCUCUGACAUAACCACAGGCUGCUGUUUUCAAGAAGAGCAAUCUGUUUGGAUAAGAAAAACCUUUACUUUACAGCUUCCCUUUAUAAUUUGUUACACAGGAAUAGUUAAAUGCAUUUGUUUGUUUGUUUUUUGAGACAGAGUUUCACUCUUGUUGCCCAGGCUGGAGGGCAAUGGCGCGAUCUCAGCUCACUGCAACCUCCGUCUCCUGGGUUCUUGAUUCUCCUGUGUCAGCCUUCUGAGUAGCUAGGAUUACAGAUGCCUAUCACCAUGCCUGGGUAAUUUUUGUAUUUUUAGUUGAGAUGGGGUUUCACCAUGUUGGCCAGGCUGGUCUCGAACUUCUGACCUCAGAUGAUCUGCCCGCCUCAGCCUCCCAAAGUGCUGGGAUUACAGGCAUGAGCCACCACGCCCAGCCAUCAAUGCAUUUUUUUUAUUUUUUUUUUGAGACAGAGUUUCGCACUUCUUGCCCAGGCUGGAGUACAAUGGUGCGAUCUUGGCUCACUGCAACCUCCACCUCCUGGGUUCAAGCGCUUCUCCAGCCUCAGCCUCCUGAGUAGCUGGGAUUACAGGUAUGUGCCACCAUGCCUGGCUAAUUUUGUAUUUUUAGUAGAGACGGGGUUUCUCCAUGUUGGUCAGACUGGUCUUGAACUCCCGACCUCAGGUAAUCCGCCCGCCUCGGCCUCCCAAAAUGCUGGGAUUAGAGGUGUGAGCCACUGUGCCCAGCCCAUCAAUGUGUUUUAAAGCUAGCUGUCAGGGUUCCACUUAAUUUAAAGCUGGGCAGGGAGAUGUGUAAUGAUUUCAAAGUUAACACCUGUUUGUUUUCUAAAGGGCAUGCCAAGUCCUGCUGUAUCAGGGAAGUAUUCUGUGCUAAAAUCAGCGAUGGUUCAUUGCUCUAGUCUCUCUCACCCUUCUAGGCAGUGCAUCAGUCAGCUCUAAAUCUGGUGCAGAGGGUUAACAGCAUAACCCUUGUUGGCAAAAUGGAAUAGAUGUUAAGACCUCAAAUAGGGAUUUGGGAUGAAACAGCUGCAGUUAGCACUGUUAUCUGAGCAUGAAAGAACUGGAAACGCUCCUUACGUCGAGAUGUUGGACCUUGAAGCCCUCCUGAGGCCAACAUGCAAAUCUGGCUGUGACGGUUCAUCUGACACCUGUGUAAAGCUGACCAGCCUGCUCUGUACAGUGACAAUGAGGAGCCCCUCUCUUCCUUAAGUAGGAAUCUGUGAAGCAAAAUGUUUGCUGCCAAAGACAAAUCAGACUGUCAGUCAUUAAAAACAGCAUUAGCAGGAUGAGGAUAGCAAUGGGGAAGGGUUGUGGGCAAUGCAGUAACAGGGAAAUGGCUUCAGAAAUGGUUUGAGUUGGAAGACAACAUUCUUCAUCUCUCAGGACUUCUAAUUCCUUGAUGCUAAAAGAAGAGGCAUGGAUUCUAUGAGCUUCCAAGUCCCUUUCCACUUUAACCUUCUACAAAUCUUUCAGAGGACUGCCUAGUAGCAAAGGUUAUUCCUGGACACAGGAAAGACGGGCAUUACAGGGACCAAAGCUCUGAAAGGUGACUUUUAUUACCAACACACUGGCUGGAAAAGGGACAAACCACAUCACGGGUGAGUGAUACUUCUCAGUCUUCUCUACUCAUUCAACAAAGGAAAUGUGGGCUGGGGCAGAGGUCUUUUUUCAUUUAAUACUGGAAAAAUAUUGAAGAGCAUCCAUGUUCACUUAUGGCUGGUUUUGCUAUAGAAAUUGGAAAAUAAAGGCCACUUUUUUGAAA